CUGUCAUGCCUAUUGCCUAGCUGCCAGAUUAACCUUGCCUUGAAAAUAACGAUUGCCCCAUAGGCUAUUCAGUGUAAGGAAGACAAAAAUUCCUUGGGAACCUACUAGUGGGUUUGCCUUCCAGAUUUGGUAGACGCAAAAAGCAAAGGGGGAACAUGGGCAAAGGAAGAUUUGAUGAAAAAGAAAAUGUGUCCAACUGCAUCCAGUUGAAAACUUCAGUUAUUAAGGGUAUUAAGAAUCAAUUGAUAGAGCAAUUUCCAGGUAUUGAACCAUGGCUUAAUCAAAUCAUGCCUAAGAAAGAUCCUGUCAAAAUAGUCCGAUGCCAUGAACAUAUAGAAAUCCUUACAGUAAAUGGAGAAUUACUCUUUUUUAGACAAAGAGAAGGGCCUUUUUAUCCAACCCUAAGAUUACUUCACAAAUAUCCUUUUAUCCUGCCACACCAGCAGGUUGAUAAAGGAGCCAUCAAAUUUGUACUCAGUGGAGCAAAUAUCAUGUGUCCAGGCUUAACUUCUCCUGGAGCUAAGCUUUACCCUGCUGCAGUAGAUACCAUUGUUGCUAUCAUGGCAGAAGGAAAACAGCAUGCUCUAUGUGUUGGAGUCAUGAAGAUGUCUGCAGAAGACAUUGAGAAAGUCAACAAAGGAAUUGGCAUUGAAAAUAUCCAUUAUUUAAAUGAUGGGCUGUGGCAUAUGAAGACAUAUAAAUGAGCCUCAGAAGGAAUGCACUUGGGCUAAAUAUGGAUAUUGUGCUGUAUCUGUGUUUGUGUCUGUGUGUGACAGCAUGAAGAUAAUGCCUGUGGUUAUGCUGAAUAAAUUCACCAGAUGCUAAAAUUCUGUUAGCUUCAGAAAUUAUUUUAAGUUUUCUUAAACUCAAGUUAAAAUUGGGUAGCAAACUUGGACAUUAAAAGGUAUCUGGUAAGUAAGCAAACUCAUACAACUAAUGUCCUUUCUUAGGCUAAUGAUAUAAGAGUGAAGAGCAGGACUUGGUCAAUGGAUUGCCAUUUUAUGGUAGACCUCUAGAGAAACUGUCUAGUUAAAUGGGGCUAGAAACUAGACUAGGAAUUUUAUUCUAUUACUCCAGGGGACCCAGCAGUGCUCAUUCUCGUGUGUGUGUGUGUGUGUGUGUGUGUAUGUGUGUGUGUGUGUGUGUGUGUGUUUUGUUGAUUGUUUUUUUAAAAAAAACUUCAAUGGAAAAUUCUAAACAUAUUAAGAAGUCUGGAGAAUAGUAUAAUGGACCUCUCCAUAUCCAUCACCCAGUUUCAGUUUAUGGUCAGUCUUAUUUCAUCUAUACCUCAAUUAUUUCUCCCCACCCCCCAAUUAUUUUGAAGCAAAUCCCAGACAUCCUAUCAUUUCAUCCAUAACUACUUUAUUCUUUUUUUUUUUUUUUUGAAACAGGGUCUUGCUCUGUUGCCCAGGCUGGAGUGCAGUGGUACGAUCUUGGCUCACUGUAACCUCCACCUCCCGGGUUCAAGCGAUUCUUGUGCCUCAGCCUCCUGAGUAGCUGGGAUUACAGGCACGUGCCACCAUGCCCGGCUAAUUUUGUAUUUUUGGUAGAGAUGGGGUUUCGCUAUGUUGGCCAGACUGGUCUUGAACUCUUGGCCUCAAGUGAUCCGUCCCCCUCUGCCUCCCAAAGUGCUGGGAUUACAGGCAUGAGCCACCGUGCCCAGCUAAUUUUUAUAUAUUUUAUAGUUGGCCAGGCUGGUCUUGAACUCCUGGCCUCAAGUGAUCAGCCUCCCAAAGUGCUGGGAUUAUAGGCAUGAGUCACCAUGCCUGGCGUCAUAACUACUUUAGUGUGUAUCUUUAAAAAUUAGAAAAACCCCACAAUACCAUUAUCACACCUAAAAAGUUGAACUGUUUCUUAAUAUGAUCAACUGUCUAGACUGUUAAUUCUCUUUAACUGUUGGUUUGCUUGAAAUAGGUACCACACAAGGUUCAUACAUUGCAUUUGGUUGUUAUUUAUUGAAGUCUGUUUAAUUUAUAAGUUACCUUUUCUUUUCCCCCUUAAAUUAUUUAAGAAAUCUAGUUGUUUUGUCUUUAAAGUUUCCACACAUAUUCUGGAUUUUGUUGAUUGUAUCACUGUGAAGUCAUUAACUUGUUUUUAUGCCUCCUGUAUAUCCUGUAAACAAAUAAGAUUGAUCAGAUUCAGGUUCAGUUUUUUUAGUGCCUUCUUUUGAGUAAAGUCAUACCAAACAGAUGCCCAGAACAUCUGGAUUUGGGUCCCCACUAGACUCCUUAAAUAAUGUAUAUCUUCUAUAAGUGGAAUAUGAGGGACAUGGACCUGCUUUAGUAAGAACAGUAAUCUGUUUGGGGAGUUAAAAGAGCAGUUGUGGAUUUAUUUAUUGAUAAAGACCAUUUUUCUUCCUAAUAACCUUGCUGUUAUUCUAGUGUCUUAGCCAUCUUCAUUUGGUUGUUUACCAAUAUAUGACAUGUGAUUUUAUUUUUCAGAUGGAUACAGACAUAUACAAGAUUGUGGUGACCUGUGUUACAGUUAGAAGUUGGUGAGAAAGGUGAGGGUGGAUAGCAAAAAGAGAGAGAUCAUUUGGCUGGCUGUUCCAGCUGGGUCUCCCAGGAUGUAACAUAGGUGGACAUAGAUCCAGGGUCUGACCCUCAGCUUGAGAAACCAUUUCCCACUGAUGAAACUUGAGAGACUUGGAGAUUCCCCAGUUAGAAUAUAAAUGUAUUAAUUCAUAGUGAUAGGUCUGCCUAUGGUAAACAAUUAGGAAACAGGAAGUUACUUGGUAAACACAGGUAUGAGCAAAGGAAGAUUGAUAAAUUGGGGUAAUAUUUCAGUUGUGCUGAGGUAAGACUUGGAGAAUUUUUCCUGCUUCAUCAUUAAUUAGAAUGCUUAUCUCUGCCAAAAUCUCAUCUCUUUCCUAGCCCAUAGAGGUGCCCUGAUAUUUUAUUUCCUAUAUCCUUUUCAAGUUCCAUGUAGUUUUCCUUAUGUUAUGACAGUUUUAUUCUGCAGCUUACCAUAUUAUUUAUUCCUGGUCCACGAAAGUAUAAAUAGUCUCAUCAGGAACUCAUUUGUAAGUCAUCUCCCAGGGGGGUUUCUUCAACAGAUAGUUUAAUUUUUUGCUGACUUACUGGCUUCAAAUUCAGAUGUCUCCCUAUUUGGGGGAGGAGGCACCCUAUUUGAGGCCUGUAGCUCCUUAUGUUCUUAAAAAGAAUAUACAAGUCAUUUAUGUCAGAAUCAAACUUUGAACCUUUAUUUUUGUUGCUAAGAGAAUGUUUUUUGACCAAGACUGCCUAUGGAGUAUUAGCAAUGAAAAACAAAGCACACAUAUACAUACAUUAGAGAAGUAAAAACUUUUAAUAGCUUGGUUUUUGAAAUAAUUCAUCUUUGUGUCUAACCACUGUUACAGUGGGUGUAAGGAACACUUUUUAAAUAUUCAACAUCAACAUCUGUGCUUGUUUUUCUACUGUGCUGAGGUACACUGUGUUGCCUUGGUGAUAUGGACUAAAUAUGUAUGUUCUCUGCUUCCCCUGGGUCUGAGGCCUCUGCUCAUCACUGUUAAUCAGGGAUGUCACUCUACAUGUGUGAUCCUUGUCAUUUUCUAAACAUUAGGUCAUACAUGAAAGGCAAUUCAAAGAGAUUAAACUAGCAGAUGUGUCAGCAUCUUUAGAUACUGUGCUUAAUGGAAACUUAGUUUACCUAUAUUCGUGAGAAUAGGAAUACAGGGAUAGAGAGCCUGCUUCUCUCAGGCAGUGUGUCUUUAGUUCAUUUUUAGUUUCAAAAUUAAGUUUGUGUCAAACCAACCUACAAUCUAGUAACUUGUGUAUUGGACUCACUUUUACUCAGACAAGGUCAGUUCAGCUCAAUAGGUAUUUAUUGAGUAUCUACUAGGUUCUAAGUGACGUGGCAUGAAGAUGAAUAAUACAGAAGUAGCCCUUGCUCUUAAGGAGCUUCCAAUCUAGUGAGUAAAGAAAAUUUACAUUUUAAAUAAUCUGGGUAAUGGUGACAGCCCAAUACUAAUAUGUAAAGCCAGUAGGAAUGUACUAAUCCUUUUCCAAUUUUAGUCAUCAAAAAUUGUAAAUUACAAAUGAACUAAAUGUAGUAAUAUUCCAUAGAUUGUAUCCAAUGUGAGGGUAAAAAAAAAAUCCCAGAUGUCUUGGAGUUGCCGUGAUUCAGCAUCCCAACUCAGAUGAUUGUCCUGUUGUCCGGUGACAUAAUGGCCUGAUCAGUUCUCUUCUAGCAGACUGUCUGUUAUGGUGGUUUGGUAGUGGUCUGUUGGGAAGCUGCAUUUUUCCUUUUCUGUUUUUAUGCUCUGGACCCCAAACAAAAACAGCUGGAUUUAUCCCAUGGGUAGUCAUGAACAUUUCCAAUUUGAGGGAUUUUAUAUUCCCCAAACAGAAGGUUAUAUGGCAUAUAUCAAAUAAUAAUGAUAUCCAGCCAGGUUCCCUGUCGUACCCAAAUCAGUAACUGAAGAUACGUAUUUCUAAGUAUAAUACUUCAGAGGAAGAGAUAAGAAUUACAAUUCACUAAAUUCGUGGAGGUGUUUCAUUAUAAUAAAUAUGUCACUUAUUAAUAAUGUAGCAAUUAUAUAUUAAUGGAAAUAUGAAUGUAUGCCCAAGCAAAAUGUCAUAAAUAUUUUAACUUUGUUUGUCUAGGUUCCUUAAUUUUGAGACUAUAAUUAUCAAGGCUCUUCAAGAAACUCAAAAUGAUUCUAAUUUCUAAGUAGUAUGCAUUAAAACUGAUAUAUAAUGAAAGAAAAACAGUGAAAAUGUAUGCAUCAGUUUCUAAAGAAAUCAUACUUGUCAUUGUAGAGAUGCAUGUAAAUUAAAUGUAUUAUACAUUUUUAUACUUGUAUGUAUUUUAUACUUUGUAUGAAUACUUUUAUUACACUUUUUAAGGCAGGUAAAAGAAUGAGUAGAUGUUAUCAACUAUAACAACAAUUUGUUGAAUACUGUGUUAAAACCAAGUAAAGGACCACAACUCCACGAGAUCAGGAAUGAAUGAAGAAAAUUGAGGGCCAGUUUUUAAAUCAUUGUUGAGACUAUUAGGUUCAUCUGUCUGUUUAAGAGUCUGGCCUUAGGGAAUAUAAUUUAUGCAUGUAAAAAAAUACAGGAGAUGAUUCACUGGAAUGUCUCUUAAUAAUACCAUGUUCAUUAAGAAUAGGUCAUUGGGAGGAAAAAUAAAUAAAAACAUCUGAACUCAUUAGUAUAAUUAAUACUUGCCUCUUAGAAUGAAAAUUAAAGAACUCCAAAUUUUAGCCUUGAAUACUUUGAGAAAUAAAAGAUGAAUUAGUGAAAUAAUUUCUACUUAAAAUCUUAGUUGUUACAGAGAAUGACAUGCCUCACUAUUAAUGUCCAAUUCUAAUUAAUGGAUUGUUUUAGAAAUGUAUUUGUGAAAUAUAGCAAACAUAGCUAGUAAUACUAACAGGUGAAAACUGAUAUUUCAAAUGACUAAAUAGACUUAAGAUUAGAGGAAGGUAGGAAAAGGUGUGCAACUAACAGAAGCAGUUAACCAAAAAAUGAGCUUCAGGCAUCAGUCUUAUUUGGAAGACUGUAAAUCAACAGGCUAACGUUCAAAAUAUGGCAGACAUCUUAAUAUCAAUAUAUGCUAAAUUGGUUUAUCUUUAGGCAGAAACAGAAAGCAAAAAAUUAAACUCAUCCAACUCAUACAUUUGUUGUUGUUGUUGUUGUUGUUGUUUUUGAGAUGGAGUCUUGCUUCAUUGCCCAGGCUGGAGUGCAAUGGCACGAUCUCGGCUCACUGCAACCUCUGUCUUCCGGGUUCAAGCGAUUCUCCUGCCUCAGCCUCCCGAGUAGCUGGGAUCCCAUGCGUGUGCCACCACACCUAGCUAAUUUUUGUAUUUUUAGUAGAGACAGGGUUUCACCAUGUUGGCCAGGCUGGUCUCAAACUCCUGACCUCAGGUGAUGCACCCGCCUUGGCCUCCCAAAGUGCUGGGAUUACAGGUGUGAACCACCACACCCGACCCAACUAAUACAUUUUUAAAAUCCCAUUUUAAAAGUAAAACCACAGUUUUCAUAUAACAAAUGUUAUUGCUCUUCAUUUCAUUCUCCAAUUUUAAAAUGCUUUACUUUCAGCCAAUAUGUGAAUAUAGGAGACUUCAAAAGCAUAAUCAAUUACUCCCUUAAAGUUCAUUGUAAGUGUUCUCAGAACUCUACCACCUAGAAUUUAAAGACGGGAAGAUUUACUUUAUAAUUUUAAUUUCUUAUCACAAGACUCGAUUGUCAAUAACUGUUAACGUCCAUUUAAUAAUCUAUGGUGAAAUAGGUAAUUUCUUCUUAUUUUCACAAGCGUGUGAGUAAAAGACUGGGUUUUAAGCAAUAAAUCAUUUGUUCUAACUAAGCACAUGCUUGGAAAAAGUGCUAUUUUUCCAAACGUAUGCCUUGAAAACAAAUACAAUUCAAUUGCCUUUUUGGUUCAUGGGAAGCCAUACUGCGGUGGCUUCCAAGGUUGGCCAACCUGUUUUUAUUCUUACCACCUCUUUCAAAAAGGGAUGUUGUCUUUGUCCCCAAAUUCUGGUGUUGUCCUAUGCUGAUGCAUAAUGAAGCCCUGAGGCUUGGAAACUUGCAAACCAAUAAGAUGAUUUAAUGAUGAAACGGCAUGUCAGUUUGACACUGUCUAUUAAUAGUCCUUGAGUGAGCUUAAAUUUGAGACACUUUUAAAAGCGGCAUGUAGUUCCAGUUUUGCUUCCCUUAUCAGUGGAGCUUGAGAUGUCUGUUCCUGCCGACUGAUGUUUUAACAAAUUUUUAGUUUCUCAUGAUGUGAAAGAUUUUGUAUGCACGUCUUAGUCUGGAUACUGUUUUCAUUAGUUCUAAUGCUGCUGCAUGCAAAUUUUGUUUAAAACCAAAAUUGACUCUUCACAUCUGGACUAGAUUGGACAUGGUGAGGAGGCUGGAAGGAAAGUCCUUUUUGCUCUGUAGGCUCUGGACAGCUUUCUUAGAGUUGACUUAUCCAGGAUUAAGAAAAAGUUUUCUUUUGCGUGACUAAAUUCUUUCCACAGUUUGCUUGUGUAAGCAUUUUAGAUUUAAGCAAGUUCAACUUGAAAUAUAUUUGAAUAUGAAGUAGAAACAGCUUCAUUUAAUGGGAUAAUAGCAAUCUCUAACCCAUCAAAUUAAUAUCUACUAAAUAGCUUCCAAAAAGCACUGACUGGAAAAUAUUUUUCACUAUCAUGGCUUUAUUCAGUUUCAAAAACAGUAGGGGCUAAAAUGUUUGGACAUUUAUCCUGCAUUUAUUUUGUGUUUCACAAGGUUAAAAUUUUGUAUUUUGUAAAGUGUCUGAAAAGGAGUCCACAAAGUAUUUCUGCUUUCUUGCUCCUGAAUGCAAAGGUCUGAGAGAAGGCACAUCCUCAUUAGCUUCUGGGUGUUGUCAAACCCAAUCCUCUCUCAAGUACCAAAUGCCCAGAUACAUUUAUUGGGAUGCAGGAAUCUCACUUAAGUAGCGGUUUUUGCUGAUAUAAAGACAAACAUCUUGAUUAAAGUGUAGGGAGAUAGAAACUAUACCAAUUUGGGCAAUUUUGGCUCUAAUGUCUAAUUUGUUGUGAAAGGGGAAGAUGUUCUAAGCUAAUGUUCUUAAAAGUAACUUAUGAAUUUCUUAAAAAUAGUUUUUAAAAAGCUGUUUCAGGAAAAGCUGUUUUAUUGCAUGGCACAGAUUAAAUGUACAGAUGUUAUCUUAAAACAAUGAAAGAGUUCCCCUAAUUUGAAUAUUCAAUACCAGCUGUUAUUCACAUCAAUAUUUUAACAUUUUACCAUCAAGAUAUUUAAUACAAAGGAUUGAUACAUAUUUAACUGUUUAGAAUUCUAGUUAAACUUGUCCAGAUGAGUAAGAGGGAAGGAGAAAUAACAUUCUCCAAGUACCUACCAUGUGCACAAGCUCUACUUAUAUAUCUUGCUUAAUCUUAGCAAUGAUUCCAUGAGGUAGAUUUUAACUCUCAUUUUACAAACGAGGAGACUAAGGCUCAGAGAGGUCAUACAACUUCAGGAAAGUUGUAUGACCUCUCUGAGGUAAUAAAUGGCAGAACUGGAAUUUGAACCUAAGUCUCCUUGUCUGCAAAUCCUGUGUUUUGCAGAAAACUCUCCUCUUGUAUUUCAUAAAAUGUUAAAUCUUGGCCCAAAUUCAAAUCACCAUCUUUAUGGGUUAUUGGAGAGAGGUAUAAGUUGGCAAGACUCUGUUCCACGAUGGGAAAAAAUGGGUAGGAUUUGAAUGAGUAAGAGUGGGAUACUUGCACAGUAUCAUAUUUGUGUGGCUGGAGUAAUGUUUUUCUGUUUCCCUCUUAGCAAAGUGGAGUGGGAGAAUCUUGAAAUUGAACUCAGUCCUGAGGUCUGAUUUUCCUAUUAUUAGUCACUUUCAAGCCAGGUGAUUUGUGACCAUUUAAAUGUUAUGCUAUUUCAAAGUCUUCUACAUCUUUAGAAAAGGACAUGAGGGAGGGUUAGUUAAGUGGGGCAAUGAGAAUGUAGAGUGUAAUGUGCAAAAGCAGGACUAGCAGUUGCUUUGAAGAUAUCUGGGGAAGGCCGGGCACGGUGGUUCACGCCUGUAAUCCCAGUACUUUGGGAGGCCAAGGUGGGCGGAUCACGAGGUCAGGAGAUCGAGACCAUCCUGGCUAACGUGAAACCCCGUCUAUACUAAAAAUACAAAAAAUUAACCGGACGCAGUGGUGGGCGCCUGUAGUCCCAGCUACUCGGGAGGCUGAGGCAGGAGAGUGGCAUGAACCCGGGAGGCGGAGCUUGCAGUGAGCUGAGAUCGCACCACUGCAUUCCAGCCUGGACAACAGAGCGAAACUCCGUCUCAAAAACCAACCAAACAAAAAACAAAAAUUAGCUGGGCAUGGUGGCGCGUGCCUGUAAUCCCAGCACUUUGGGAGCCAAGGUGGGUGGAUCAUGAGGUCAGAAGAUUGAGACCACCCUGGCCAACAUGGUGAAAUCCUGUCUCUACUAAAAAUACAAAAAAAAAAAAAAAAAAAAAAAUUAGCCGGGCGUGGUGGCGCGUGCCUGUAAUCCCAGCUACACAGGAGGCUGAGGCAGGAGAUUUGCUUGAACCUGGGAGGCGGAGGUUGCAGUGAGCCGAGAUUGUGCCACUGCACUCCAGCCUGGGCGACAGAGCAAGACUCCGUCUAAAAAAAAAAAAAAGAUAUUAAAAUUAAUGACAGGAAGAGUUUGGGUUCAGUUAUAAUUUAAGGGAAAAAACAUUGAGGGGCCUAAUCUACAUUUUGCUCCGGAUCCAAUGAUUUAAUUUUUGGGAAGAAAAAUCCAGUGAUUAAAGUCAUGCAAGGAGAUGGCCUGGGGCUUGCUAAAAGUCAGGUUGCAGUUUCCAUUGCAUUCAAGAAAAUCAGAAAAAUAAAUACAACUUUUAGAAGAAACUAAGUUUUCUCCCAUUCAUGUUUAGCUAUUGGGGGGUCUCAUACUUCUGGACUUGCUUAGACCUAUGCUAUCUAAUAUGGUAGCCUCUGCCCAUCCAUAUGUGGCCACUGAGAACUUGAAAUGUGACUAGUUUGAAUUAAGAUGUGCUGUAACUAAAAUACACCCUGGAUUUCAAAGACUUAAUAAAUAAUGUAAAUUAUCUAUUCUUUCCUGUUGAUUAUAUAUUGAAAUGAUAAUAUUUUGGAUAUGUUUGGGUUAAAUAAAAUAUAUUACUAAAAGUAA